CCCCUUCCGGGCCCCCGCCAGCUGAGGGGAGCCGCCGACUGGAGCCGCCGUCCGGCUCCCCGGCCCCCCAAACAAAGGACCCGCCGGGUCCUAGUGCCCGCCCGCUCCGUCACCUUCGCGCCUCCGGGUCCUAGCGCCUGCUCACCGCUCGCAGCCCACCCUGCCAACCUCUGCCUCUGCCAGUCGCUAAUACCUGCCCCCAUAUAGGCUUGCCUUUAUCUUUCUCCUUGCCUGCUGCCCCUCAGCUCGCGACCCUCCUGCACCUGCCUCCAGCUUUCCCUGUCCGCAACAGUCCUCCACGUGUUUCCCACGCACCCCACUUCUGUGCCCCCUUCCUCACCCCCCUUGUUCCUUCGCCUUUUGCCCCACACCUCCUGCUCCUUUUCGGCAUUUGCCUGCAGCUGCAGUGCUUUUAGACCCCCGCCCUCUCCGCGUUAGUUCGUCCGUCCAUCCAUCUAUCCUCCCUCCCUCCAUCCUUCGGUCCAUCCAUCCAUGCCUCCAACCCACUGUCCUUUCCCAGGCCUCUUGCCCUGCCUCUUGGCUCUCUGCUCUUACUCUCACCUUCUCUAGGCCCCUGAGUGCCUUAGUGAGCGGGCCUACAGCCCCUUCUUCUGAUCUUUGUCUUCUGGGCCCCAGGGAGCACCUGGCCUCGUGGCCUUUCGGGGUGACAGCAGGCAUCACGCCCCUGAAGAAGUUUGCAAAAACUGAGGUACAAGGGCAACCCCUGCCCAAAGGCCCUCUAAGAAGGGGAGGGACUUGCAUAGCUGACCAAGGAGACUUUGAAGAUGCUCAAGGACCAAAGACAGCAGUUUCUCUGCUCUGUGACCAUCCUAUCAGUGCAGGACCUGAGAAGCUGGGUGUAACUUUGACAAUGCUAUGGUAACCCAGGUGGAGCAAAAUUGAGUUCAUGGGGGUGGGGACCUGGGAGAGUAUCUAUUUGGGAUGCCACAUAGUAGCAGAAAGGACCCAUCGAGAAAUCUCAAGAAGAGACUCAGGGACUUAUAGAAACAUUGGUUAAGGACGGUUUCCCCUUUAAAUGGGGAAGCAGGCCCAGAAAAGAGAUGAUACUUACCCACAAUCACCCAACUAGUUAGCAGUGGAACCCUAAACUGCACCUUGAAGUGAAGGGUCCCAUAAGAAAGGUGGAUGGAUUCUUCUUAGUGGGGCCAUCUUAGUCCAGAUGCAGCAGGUGAAGGAAGAUGGGCAUUUGAGAAUGGACCCACUGAAAGGUUCCCCAAGUGGUCCUAGCACCAGGAGCUUGUCACGGAGUGUGGGCUUCAUACUGUUGAGCUGCAGGCCCUGCUUGGGGCUUCUGGAAAGGGGACAACCUCUGGGUUGUCUUCUGGGAAGAACAGUCUCUGGUAAGGAGAGGCUGGAGACUCUCUAAAACUGGCCCUGACCCUUCUGAGCUGUGUUUCUCCUCUAGGGGCUGAGCUGGAGGAGAGUAGCAAAAACACGAAGAAGUUGGAUGCCAUGACCCUCAUUAAAGAAGACAUGUCCAUCUUCGGGCACUGCCCUGCCCAUGAUGACUUCUACUUGGUUGUGUGUAACCACUGCAGCCAAGUGGUGAAGCCUCAAGCUUUCCAGAAGCACUGCGAAAGAAGACAUGGGCCCCUCAGCAAGCUUUAUGGCCGGGCCCCACCCCCACCUCCAGCCCCUGCCAGCUCUCAGAAAUGCCAUGUAGUGAAUGGGCAGGGCCCAGCUUGUAGGGCCCCAGGUUCCACGAAAACCUCCUCCAGGGAGAAGGGCCAGGGGUCCCGGAGCCGUGGCCACCAGCCUCCUGAGAAGACCCAGAAGGACAACCUCUGCCUUUUCGUGCCUGUGGUGAAUCUGGAGAAGAUGUCCAGUCUCCCGAAGCCUGAUGGACAUGGAAUCAGGGUGGCCCCACCCUCUGCUUUUCUCAGCCAGCCAGGGGGCCUCACCAAGGACUCCCCUGGAAAACCUCCCAUGGCUCCCCCUUCUAAAGAACCUCCUGGCAGAGAGAACAUCGAGAUCAUCCCCAGUGAGGGGUCCAGUCACUGGGCUGAAGGCAGCCCUCCUGAAAAGGAGCCCAGUGGGACCAGGCUGCCCCCUAAAACCCACCGGAAGAUGGCUCGGAAGGAGUGCGACCUCAACAGGCAGUGUGGGGUAAUAAAUCCAGAGACCAAAAAGAUCUGUACCCGCCUGUUGACCUGCAAGAUCCACUCAGUACACCAGCGCCGGGAAGUCCAGGGCCGGGCCAAGGACUUUGACGUGCUGGUGGCAGAGCUGAAGGCCAACUCCCGCAAAGGGGAGUCUCCCAAGGAGAAGAGCCCAGGGCGCAAGGAGCAAGUUCUCGAGCGCCCCUCCCAGGAGCUCCCCUCCUCAGUCCAGGUUGUAGCAGCGGUGGCUGCUCCCAGCAGCACCUUCUCUGUUCGUGCCAAGCAGACCUACCCAUACUGUGCACUGCCCAGGUCCCGGGCCUCCUCCGAGAGUGAAUUGGAUGAUGAAGGCCCCUGUGGUGGUGAUGGGGACCCAGGCCUGUUCCCCUUCCCCAUGCCCCGGGGUGGGACCCAGGCCUCCAGCGAAGAGAGUGAGGAGGAGGGGACAUCUGACGACCUCCACCCACCCCCUGACUGCCAUUAUGCAACCCGGCCCCCACGGCCACAGGCGUUCUGCACCUUUGGGAGCCGGCUGGUGAGCCCAGGAUGCUAUGUGUUUAGCCGCCGGCUGGACCGGUUCUGCUCAGCACUCAGCUCCAUGCUGGAACGGCACCUCAGCACACACAUGUGGAAGAAGAUCCCACCGGCAGCUGAACCUCCAGCUCACCUUGUCAACUCCCCGUUAUCUGCUCCCCUGAGCCCAUCCUCUACAGGCACCUGCCCCCGCCUUCCAGGUCCAACCCUGAGACCUGCCUGCCCAGCCUCCAUGCCCCCCACCAAGGACAACCUUGUCCCCAGCUACCCUGCAGGCUCCCCCAGCGUGGCGGCUGCCUGUAGCCAGGCAGAGUGCAUGGGCGGGAGCCAGGCUAUCACCUCACCACUGCCUGCCAACACGCCAUCCCCGUCCUUCAGCAAGCUGCCGCCUUCCAAGGCCAGCAAGUCAUCCAAAGGCAAGGACGGGGUGGAGGUGGAGGCCCCUUCUCGAAAGCGGAAGUUAUCCCCUGGCCCUACCACUCUUAAACGGACCUGCAUCCUGGAGCCCACUGGAAAAGGGAAACCCUCUGGCUGUAGGGGCCUCUCGGCCAAAACUAAAACAGCCCUGAGCAUGGGGCUUAAUGGGACAAUGGGGCCAAGAGUGAAGCGGGCAGGGCCCCUGGACUGUCGUGGCUCCCCUCAUCAGCUCCCCACACCAGUCAAGGCUUCUCAGCUGGAGAACCGGGGAGCAGCUGGACACCCAGCCAAGGCCCUGCCAACCAACUGCCUCUCUGAGGAGGAGGUGGCCAAGAAGCGGAAAAACCUGGCCACUUAUUGCCGGCCAGUGAAGGCCAAGCACUGUCAGGCUGGUGCCCCUGCUGAUGUGGCCUGCUCUGUGCGCCGCAAGAAGCCAGGCCCGGCCCUGGCCUUUGAGGAGAAGUGCUCUACACUGAAGGUACUGGAGCUACCUCUGUUCCCUGAAGGAAAGGGAGUUUGAGUCCCUGGGUCACAGCCUAACAUGCCGAGCAGCAAGUCAAAAGCCCAUUAACGAGAAAGUGCCUGCCCACUGCAACGGAGCCGCCAGCACCUCCUCCCCUCCAGAUCCGGGCCCCAGGCUGCUGCCGCUUUUUAUAACUUUAUAUUAUUUUUUUUUAAGAAAAAAAGCUCUUUAAAAUACCUCAAGACUGUCUCCCUGUUCUGUUGCUGCUAUGAAAAUAUAAAAACAGAAACAUAGAAAAGGAAGGAAAAAAAA